AUGCACUUCCCGCUACGCCUCGGUGCAGCCCCCGGCGAAGCCCAGCGCAGCUCAGCUAAACUCAGCGGAGCCAGCGCGGCGCGAUGGAAGGUCGAGUGCAGCUGAUGAAGGCCCUCCUGGCUCGGCCCCUCCGGCCCGCGGCGCGUCGCUGGAGGAACCCGAUUCCCUUUCCCGAGACGUUUGAUGGCGAUACCGACCGGCUCCCGGAGUUCAUCGUGCAGACGAGCUCCUACAUGUUCGUGGACGAGAACACGUUCUCCAACGACGCCCUGAAGGUGACGUUCCUCAUCACCCGCCUCACGGGGCCCGCCCUGCAGUGGGUGAUCCCCUACAUCAAGAAGGAGAGCCCCCUCCUCAGUGAUUACCGGGGCUUCCUGGCUGAGAUGAAGCGGGUCUUUGGAUGGGAGGAGGACGAGGACUUCUAGGCCGGGAGACCCUCGGGCCUGGGGACCGGUGCUCUGGGAAGGGUCCGCUGUGUUACUGGCCGCCGCCAGGGUCGCCACCGGCGCCCUCCCUCCGCGCCUCCCUCCCCCUCGAGCCGCCACGAUGUCCCCUGCGCUCCUGUCCCCUCCCGCGUAGUGCUUGCCUUUGUUCCAGGAAUAGCGCUCCAGGCUCCUGCUGCCGCCCCUGGGCCUCACUCUGGAGCGGGCUGCCUCCGCCCUCUCGUGCCAGCUCAGCCCCUCCCAUGCACAUUUGGACGCUGUCCUGCGCUCCAGUUGCACAAAGCUGAGCUCCUGUUACACACUGACAGACCACUGACAGCCGCCGCUGCCAACCCCCCUCCUCCUCACCAGACUUCCAGACGACUACAUCAUGCUGCCCACAGACCUGCGCUGCCACUGCCAUCGCCAUCCAUCGCAUUCCACCGACAGACUGCUGCUUCUAGUGAUCUGUACUCACCUCGGAGGUAUCUGGGCUGGACACAGCCCCUGGACAAUGAUCCAGACAGCUGGCUGCCCCUCAAGGGACCUGUUACCUUCAGCGAGACCCAUUUCCUCCCCAAUCCCAGAGACUUUUUGUGCUCCUGCCACAUGGCUGCCAGGGCUCAGUUGUGCCUGGCAGCCAAAUCGAGUCUCUCAUUUUCUCUUGUGGACCAGUUAGUUUUGCCCAGAAUCCAUUUCUCUUCUGAAUUUGCAGCAUUUUCUCAGGUGCUUUUUGAUCAACAAAAUAACUUGUAUCUUCUGCUUAACUCCUUUAUACUACCUGGAGAAAAGUAUUUUCCAUAUUUUCAAUAAAUGUCAGACACUAUUGAGAAAGAAAUAGAGUCUGAAUGAAUAUGGCACCUUUCCCUCCCUGGUCCUGUAAAUGUGGUCCAUAUCUUGUUCAGAAGCGAUAUCCCCUGCCAUUCAGUGACUGAUGUUGACUCCUGCAUUAUAAAACAUCUAAGAUAGAGUCCUGUGGUAACCUGGGGGAUAGUGUCCCCACUGGUGAUCCUUCUGUCCCAGAUGUUGAAUCCUCUAAACCAGUUAGGAUUAUCCCAAGCCUCUUAGUAAAUGAAUCGUUACCUCAUUUUGGUCAACACUAUGUGAGAAGUCAGCCAGCAGGCUCUUGGAAAAUGUAUCCUCAUUUCCAGAAAGUGGUUUGAAAACACAAUUCCCAAAUUGUUACAAACCAUAAAUCCCACACAGAUUAUUGGUGAACAGCUGUAAAAUUUUACUCAACCCAUGAUUCAGGGAACCAACAGAAUUAUAUAGGUGCUUUUCAAAAGCAUUUAUAAAUUCUUGAUUAUGUAGGUAGUGGGGGGAAAUGCAGAAAUGAGAUCAUUAAUUUAGAUACAAACCUGGUUGAUGACCAGGGGGUUUUAUUUUGCAGAAGAAUUGGGUAUUUGGUAUCAUUUUAUUCAAUUACAUGUGAUCCUGGUACAUUUCAUAAGCUUGGGUAAAAAAAUUUUUUGUUAUUUUCCAUGCACAAUAAGGGAAAUGUUUUAAUUGGCUUUGUGCCUCCUGCUUUACAACAGUUCUGGCCUCAAGUUACCAGGUAGCCUGAACUUUGAUUUUAUUUUACCAUUAAAUUGCUUUAAUACCAUUGUA